CACUGGGUGGCGCUGCCCGCUCGGCCCGGCGCUCCUGGAGCUGCGAGCCGCGACCGCCGGGAGCGCACCUGCCCCGCCUCCGCCAGGCGGUCCGCGGGGCAUGCAGCGGACCGGGGGCGGGGCUCCGAGGCCCGGGCGCAACCACGGGCUCCCAGGCAGCCUCCGCCAGCCGGACCCCGUCGCCCUCCUGAUGCUGCUCGUGGACGCUGAUCAGCCGGAGCCCAUGCGCAGCGGGGCGCGCGAGCUCGCGCUCUUCCUGACCCCCGAGCCUGGGGCCGAGGCGAAGGAGGUGGAGGAGACCAUCGAGGGCAUGCUCCUCAGGCUGGAAGAGUUUUGCAGCCUGGCUGACCUGAUCAGGAGUGAUACUUCACAGAUCCUGGAGGAAAACAUCCCAGUCCUUAAGGCCAAACUGACAGAAAUGCGUGGCAUCUAUGCCAAAGUGGACCGGCUAGAGGCCUUCGUCAAGAUGGUUGGACACCACGUCGCCUUCCUGGAAGCAGACGUGCUUCAGGCUGAGCGGGACCAUGGGGCCUUCCCUCAGGCCCUGCGGAGGUGGCUGGGAUCCGCAGGGCUCCCCUCCUUCAGGAACAAGUCACCUGCACCGGUGCCCGUGACGUACGAGCUGCCCACACUGUAUAGGACGGAGGACUAUUUUCCUGUGGACGCCGGGGAAGCACAGCACCACCCCCGCACCUGCCCUCGGCCUUUAUGAGUUUCCUGCUAUUGUCCUAACACUCCGGAUUUCUCACUGUGGCUUCAACCUGCAAUGGGUAUUUCUGGAAUUCCUCGAAGAGCCAAGAACACACACAUAAUUCCCCUAUGCACAUACAGGACUGAACUGUAAAUCUGCAUUAGAAUUUCAAGAUAAUCUGCCUGGGCAAGGUGACUCAUGCCUGUAAUCCCAGCAUCUUGGGAGGCUGAGGCAGGAGGGUCGCUUAUGCACAGGGUCAAGACUGCAGUGAGCCGUGAUUGUUCUACUGCACCCUAGCAUGUGCAACAGAGCAAGACCCUGUCCCCCACACCCCAAAAAAGUUUUUCAAGGAAGCCUAAAAUAAUGAAUCUGGCAAGAUAGAGUAGAGGCCAGGUGCAGCGGCUCAUGUCUGUGAUCCCAGCACUUUGGGAGGCCGAGGCAGGCAGAUCGCCCAGGAGUUUGAGACCAGCCUGGGCAACAUAAUGAGACCAUAUCUCUACCAAAAAUACAAAAAUUAGCCUGGCGUGCUGGUGCACAUCUGUGGUCCCAGCUACUUGGGAGGCUGAGGUGGGAGGAUUGCUUGAGCCUGGGAGGUUGAGGCUGCAGUGAGCCAUGAUUGUGCCACUGCACUCUAGCCUGGGUAACCAAGUGAGAUCUUGGCUAAAAAUGUUUUUAAAAAUUAAAAACAGAAAAGCAGGGAAAUAGUUUAGACAAUUUUUGGAAUUCAGAGAUAUAGGUAGACCCCUUGUUUCUGGAAAAGUCAGCAUUUUUAUUCUCUUUUCUUUUUUUUCGAGAUGGAGUCUCACUCUGUCACCCAGGCUGUAGUGCGGUGGCAUGAUCUCAGCUCACUGCAACCUCCGCCUCCCGAGUUCAAGCUAUUUUCCUGCCUCAGCCUCCCAGGAAGCUGGGAUUACGGGAGCACACCACCACGCCCAGCUAAUUUUUGUAUUUUUAGUAGAGACGGGGUUUCGCCAUGUUGGUCAGGCUGGUCUCGAACUCCUGACCUCAGGUGAUCCUCCUACUUUGGCCUCCCAAGGUGCUGGGAUUACAGGUGUGAGCCACCAUGCCCGGUCAGCAUUUUUUUAUUGAGGUGACUUUUACAAUUUUUUUUUUCUUUAAAUGAGACACCUGUCACCCAGCCUGGAGUGCAGUGGUGUGAUCAUGGCUCCCUGAAACCUCAAGCUCCUGGGCUCAAGUGAUCCUCCUGCCUCAGCCUCCCAAGUAGCUGGGACCACAAAUGUGCACCACCAUGCCUGGCAACUUUUCAAAUUUGUUUUAUUUUUUGUAGAGACAGGGUCUCCCUAUGUUGUUCAGGCUGGUCUUGAACUUCUGGGCUCAGGGGACCCUCCUGUUUCGGCCUCCCAAAAUGUAGUGUUGGCACAAACCUUUAUUGAAGUAUAAUUUAUAUUACAGAAAGGGGUGCCUAAGUGGUUCACUAAAUUUUUCACAAACUGAGUGUAUCUAUUUAAGCCUCACCAGACUGAGCAACCAACAUUAUCAGCACUGAGCAGCCCCCUCAUGCCCGCUUCUGGUCCAUGCCCAUACCCACCCCCACCCCAGGCUGACAGCAUACUGACAUCUAACCAUAUGGACUGGAGUUUCUUGUUUCUGUGCUCUGUAUAAAGAGAGGACACACGGGAUGUGUACCUACGGUGUGUCAUCUCUUGUCUCUGGCCUCACCGGCUUGAUGUUACCUUGGGAGGUGUCACUGUUGCUGUGUCACUGUAGAUCAUUCCCAUGGCUGUGUUGUAUUGGCUGGGACUGUUUUUAUCGAAGGGAGCUUGGACACUCUGCAUGCCCCAGUGUGCUCAGGGAGAGCACACGUUGGAUGGAAAGUUGGCCGGGUGAGGUGGCUCACGCCUGUAAUCCCAGCACUUUGGGAGGCCAAGGUGGGCAGAUCACUUGAGGUCAGGAAUUCGAGACCAGCCUGGCCAACAUAGUGAAACCUCAUCUCUACUAAAAAUACAAAAAUUAGCCAGGUGCUGUGGUGCACCCCUGUAAUCCCACCUACUCGGGAGGCUGAGGCAGGAGAAUCGCUCGAAUCUGGGAGGUGGAGGUUGCAGCAAGCCAAGAUCGUGCCACUGCACUCCAGCCUGGGCAACAGAGCGAGACCCUAUCUCAAAAAAGAAGAAAAAGGAGAAAGCUAAUGUUAAUUUUUUAGACAAGCAGUUGAGGACACUCAUUUCCGGAAGGGUGAGUAUCUGCUGAGUGUUGGGCACUCCCAGGCUUCUUUCUCCUCCCAGCCCCUGAAACAGGGGCCAGGGAGAGUUGGAAGGAAAUCCCAUGUGAUUAAGCCGCAGCAACGUUGAGUGUCCUAAAGCAGGGACCCACAGGCCCCACGCUAGGAGCAUGGCCCUGAGGUUAGCCUGCCUGGCAGCACUGUCCGCUCCCAUGCCUCUUAGCUGUGUGAGCUGGGCUUUUCACUUGCUCUCUCUGAGUCCAGCUGCCCCUGCGGUAAGACAUGAGGAUGGCUCUGGUCUGAUGGGUUGUGGUGAGGGUGACAUGAGGUGAGCUGUGUGCAUGCUGGGCACACUGGCGAGGGGCUCUCAGUAAUGGGAGGCUGCUGUUGCAGGGCCCGGGCUGUGAUGGGGAAAGGGUUGAUUGUCCUGCGUUUCUCAGUUGACCAGCGGCAUCCGAGGGCCUGAACAGCGAGUGACUCAGGGACUGCCCUUACGUGUCAGAGUUAGAAGUCAUGGGAGAAUGGAGGCUGCUCUCUCUGGGUUUCCCUGUCCUGUUAGGAGGGGUGAGGUUGCACAGGAAAUCUAUGGGGAAAAGGUGACAAGUGAACUGGAAGUAGCCGUUCCAAAGUUCCUAGGAUUUGCACUGCCAAACAAUGAGCUUUAAGGGACGCUUGGAAACAUCUGGGGAGAAGGAAGGCCGGGACACUGCGCCCUGCCAUCACCAACCCCUAACCUCAGUCCUCUGAGCGGCUCCACUGUCCCUGUGCCAGGUGACUUCAUGUGCGUCCUCAUUAAAGCAAAGUGCCUGACAUUUCCAUUGUCCAGUCAAUGAUGUCCUCGGUUGCUGACUAUUGAUGGCCUCUAACCCCUUGGUAAGGGUAACUGCAGCCUAGGAAAGGGUGAUCUGAUCUUUCUCUUUUUUAAACAGAGACGGGGUUUUGCUAUGUUGUCCAGGCUAGUCUCAACCUCCUGGGCUCAAGCGAUCCUCCUACCUUGGCCACCCAAAGUAUUGGGAUUACAGUCGUGAGCCACCGAGGCCUGCCAGUCUUUUUCUUUUGUGGCUGAUGUUGGACAGGGACACCAGUAGAAAGGUCACUGCAGAUUUCUUCCCAAGAGCAAGGCUCUUCGGUCAACCCCCUUUCCCACUUUCCCAGCGGAUGUGAACUUCGUGCUCACCAAAGCAAGAGGUUUCAAGGUAGCAGCCCAUGGGGUUGUAUCUGAUUGGCAGAAAUGUGUGGUUUGCCCUGAAUUGUUUUAAGAUGUUUUCAUGUUGUGACAAUUGGGUAAACUUCUGGAAAAAAUAGAGCUCCAUACCUCACUCAGCACACCUGGAUUGUAAAUCGAUUAGGAGCUUAAUGUAUAAAAUGAAUCUAUUGGCCGGGUGCAGUGGCUCACACCUGAAUCCUACCACUUUGGGAGGCCAAGGUGGGUGGAUCGCUUGAGCUCAGGAGUUCAAGACCAGCAUGGGCAACAUAGCAAAACCCCUUCUCUGUAAAAAAUAGAAAAAUUAGCCAGGCAUGGUGGUGCUUGCCUAUAGACCCAGCUACUUGGUGGGAGGUGGGAAGAUUGCUCGAGCCAGGGAACUUGAGGCUGCAGUGAGCUGAGAUUGUGCCACUGCACUCCAGCCUGGGUGACAAAGUGUUACCCUGUCUUAGAAAGUAAAAUAAAACGAAUCUAUUGAAGAAAUAGGUUAAAAACAUUGGCGAAGUGUACAAAAUCGAGAAGCCAUAAAAGAGGUCAAUUUGAUUAUAUAAAAUUUUUAAACUUCUGCAUGGCAAAACCAACGGAAAACUCAACCAAAAAAUCCCAAAACAACAAAAUCCUAAGCAAAUUCAAAAGAUAGAUGACAAAUUGGGAAAAUAUAUUUGCAUCUCAUGCUACAAAGGGAUAAUCUCCCUAAAAAAUGUCACCUACAAAAAAGGGAAACAGUAGCAAAACAGGCAAAGGCUAUGAACAGGAGUUUCACAGAAAAUGCAAAACAUGAAAAGAUACUCAACCUUAAUGUAUGCCAAUAAGUAUGGAAAAAUACCCUGAGAUUUUUCACAUUUCAGGCUGGCAAGGAUUAAAAUUUUUGAUGACACUAUUGAAUUUUUUUUUUUUUUUGAGACAGAGUCUGCUCUGUUGCCCAGGCUGGAGUGCAGUGGUGUGAUCUCAGCUCACUGCAACCCCUGCCUCCUGGGCUCAAAUGAUCCUCCCACCUCAGGCACCCAAGUAGCUGGGAUUACAGGUGCGCACCACCAUGCCCAGCUAAUUUUUGUGUUUUUAGUAAAGAUGGGGUUUUGCCAUGUUGGCCAGGCUGGUCUCAAACUCCUGGCCUCAAGUGAUCCACCUGCCUCAGCCUCCUAAAGUGCUGGAAUUACAGGCUUGAGCCACUGUGCCUGGUCUUGCUGGUGAUAUUUUGAAGAAACAUAUUCUUGUACAUUGAUGGUGGGACACCAUUCUCAUGGGGGGGCAAUUGGCAUACCUAACAAAAUUAGAAAUGGUCCUAGCUACUCAGUAGGCUGCGGCAGCAGGAUCGCUUGAGUGAGCCCAGGAGGUUGAGGCUGCAGUAAGCCGUGAUCAUGCCACUGCACUCCAGCCUGGAUGACAAAGCAAAACCCAAUCUCUUAAAAAAAAAAGGGGGGGUUGCGGGGGGAAAUGUCCUCAGACCCAGUAAUUCCACCCCUAGGAAUCCAGCUUACACACACAAGAAAGAAAAGAUAAAUGUACAAGGUUAGUCACUGCACAGUGAGACAGCAAAAGAUUAGAAAGAACCCAAGUGAUUAUUGAUCUGGGUUUUAUUCCUUUAUAGCCCAACCAUAUGAUGGAAUACUAUAAUGUUGUAAAAAUGGGUUAAGAGUUCUUUAUGAAUUGGUGUGGAAACAUCGCCAAGAUAUGAAAGCCAAAUGCAGAAAAAUAUAUGUGGUAUGCUAUUAUCUAUGUGAAAAAGACAUUACUAUUCUCUGGAAGGAUAAACACAAAUUUGAGAAUGGUGGAUAUCUGGGGUGAGAGGUAUCCUUUUCACUGUUCUUUAAAAGUUUUGAUAUUUUGGUGUUUGCCUAUUCAAAAAAAUGGUUAAAAUCAGUUGCCACCAAUUAAAAAUUAGGAGAAUGCAUAUAAA